AGAUGCCUCGCCAGGCCACGUCGCGGUUGGUGGUCGGAGAGGGCGAGGGGUCCCAGGGGGCUUCGGGGCCUGCAGCCACCAUGCUCCGCUCCCUGCUGCUUCACUCCUUGAGGCUCUGCGCCCAGACCGCCUCGUGCCUCGUGCUCUUCCCGCGCUUCCUCGGCACGGCCUUCAUGCUCUGGCUUCUCGAUUUCUUGUGUAUCCGCAAGCAUUUCCUGGGCCGCCGCCGCCGGGGGCAGCCCGAGCCCGAAGUGGAGCUCAACAGUGAAGGCGAGGAGGUGCCUCCCGAUGACCCGCCCAUCUGCGUGUCCGACGACAACCGCCUGUGCACCCUGGCGUCGCUCAAGGCGGUGUGGCAUGGCCAGAAGUUGGAUUUCUUCAAGCAGGCGCACGAGGGCGGUCCGGCGCCCAACUCCGAGGUGGUUCUGCCCGACGGCUUCCAGAGCCAGCACAUCCUCGACUACGCGCAAGGGAACCGCCCGCUGGUUCUCAAUUUCGGCAGCUGCACCUGACCACCGUUCAUGGCGCGCAUGAGCGCCUUCCAGCGCCUGGUCACUAAGUACCAGCGCGACGUCGACUUCCUCAUCAUCUACAUCGAGGAAGCGCACCCCUCCGACGGCUGGGUCACCACGGACUCUCCCUACAUCAUCCCACAGCACCGGAGCCUGGAGGACCGGGUCAGCGCAGCGAGGGUACUGCAGCAAGGUGCACCCGGCUGCGCUCUGGUCCUCGACACCAUGGCCAACUCCAGCAGCUCGGCCUAUGGCGCCUACUUCGAGCGUCUCUAUGUCAUCCAGAGUGGCACUAUUAUGUACCAGGGCGGCCGUGGCCCCGACGGCUACCAGGUCUCUGAGCUGCGCACUUGGUUGGAACGCUAUGAUGAGCAACUGCACGGCGCUCGGCCCCGGAGGGUGUAAACAUCCAACGGACAAUUGACUGAACUUGGUGGGCUGGGCCUUCGAGCCUUCGAAGCCCACGUGCAAGCGCCUCAAACCAAGUCACGCUUGGCGAGGCCCCAGUGACACUGAUGUGCUGAGCCACCAUUUCAGACUGAGUCUGCACCCUCAGCCACAUGAACAAUCUCCCCUACCUCCCUGGGACUCUGCUUCUGUAACUGUCUCAUUCACACCUGCCUGGCUCACUGGAAAUCCUCUUUUGAGCGCGGGAUAUGGCUUGCCCUUGUCCGUGUGCCCCCAGGACUUUGCCUCUACAGCAUUUUCUUACACCCCCUCCCCAGCGUGCCCUCAGCCAAGUGCUUUGGCCCGGUGCUUCCCGCAGCUGCACAGAGACCUUGGCCACGCCCGCGCGCCCUGAGCGCAGCUGGGUUCCAGGAGACUCUCAGCUCAGCUGAGCUAGUUGCCUGGCACCCACCUGUCGCGCGCGGAGAGGGGGUUCCCUGUUGCUUUUGUGUCUGUUUCCUGUCCCUGGUAGGGGAAGUGAUGUCGUGGAUGGGGAGGGGUGGGCAGGGUAGUUUCCCCCGCUUGUUUUGGGUGCACAGGAGCCCCACUGCUGAUGACGAACUAUCUCUAACUGGUCUUGACCACGAGCUAGUUCUGAAUUGCAGGGGCCUCAAAGCAGCACCUAAACCUUGAGGGGGAGGGUGCUCUGGGUUUCCGUGAGGUAACCACCUUAAAUGGGAGGGAAGUUGGGGUGUCUGCUUUGGGACCAGAGGAAGAUAGCUUGAGAGGCAUUGGCGAGGUUCGCAGCGCCCCAGGGAGAGAGAAAAAGCUGAGACUCCUGGGGAAUGACGUUGGGGUGAUGGAGUCCGGGGAAAGAGAGGUGGGGGGAGAGCCUGAGGUCCCCAAGUGAGGGGAGUCCUAGGCAGAGCUGCUGAUUGUGGGGCUGGGAGGUGGAGGGCCCCUGAUUCGAAGGCCAUUUGGUGAGUGUUUUGCUGGAAAUAUUUCCUGUAUAUAAACUUCUUUCAAUCUACAAUAAUAAAGGCUUGAGGUAAACUGCUU